ACUCGCCCCAGCCGCCGCCAUGAAGGCCGUGGUGCAGCGCGUCACCCGGGCCAGCGUCACAGUUGGAGGAGAGCAGAUUAGUGCCAUUGGAAGGGGCAUAUGUGUGUUGCUGGGUAUUUCCCUGGAGGAUACGCAGAAGGAACUGGAACACAUGGUCCGAAAGAUUCUAAACCUGCGUGUAUUUGAGGAUGAGAGUGGGAAGCACUGGUCGAAGAGUGUGAUGGACAAACAGUACGAGAUUCUGUGUGUCAGCCAGUUUACCCUCCAGUGUGUCCUGAAGGGAAACAAGCCUGAUUUCCACCUAGCAAUGCCCACGGAGCAGGCAGAGGGCUUCUACAACAGCUUCCUGGAGCAGCUGCGUAAAACAUACAGGCCGGAGCUUAUCAAAGAUGGCAAGUUUGGGGCCUACAUGCAGGUGCACAUUCAGAAUGAUGGGCCUGUGACCAUAGAGCUGGAAUCGCCAGCUCCCGGCACUGCUACCUCUGACCCAAAGCAGCUGUCAAAGCUCGAAAAACAGCAGCAGAGGAAAGAAAAGACCAGAGCUAAGGGACCUUCUGAAUCAAGCAAGGAAAGAAACACUCCCCGAAAAGAAGACCGCAGUGCCAGCAGCGGGGCUGAGGGCGACGUGUCCUCUGAACGGGAGCCGUAGCUCAGGAGGCAGAAUUCAGUGUGUUAUCAUUGGGCAGAACUGGAUCCUGAAAAAUUCAAGAUGCUAAGCACCUACACUACUUUAAGAAUUUGGAACUGAAACAUGAAGAGGAAGACAGAAAUAAGAAUUUGGGAACCUGAAUAGCUCUGCAAAAAACACCAAAGGACCGUUUUAUCGUUUUCUGUUGUUGCUGUGGUGGAGUGAUGCAGUGGGCACUGCCGGUGGGCCAGGGGGCGGGUGCGCAUGUGGUAGAAGGUGUGCGCUCGUGCCUCCCCCACAGAAAGGCUUUGUUGGUUUCUACCACAUCUUGGCUUGCUUUUGGAACAGGCUGGCCCAGCAUCAUUUGUCAUCAAGUCCACUGUGGUGUAUUCUGCGUGUCCAUGGCGGGGGUUCUCCAAUACACUCACACUGUCCAUGUUCUUUUUAUUGCCAGGGCCCGUGUUGAAGUGUCAAGAGAGCAAUCAUCAAUGAUAAUGUAUUGUGUGAGACCUUUGCAUCUUGUAAAUUUUCUCUUUUUUCUAAAAAUAAAUAAUAAUAAAAUCCUAAAUCUCAACAAACCACUUUAUUAUCAAACAAAUUCUGCUCUGUUUCUGCAUAACGAUGAUGUCCAUAGAAAUGCAAUGCGUCUGACCUCUCUCUAUGCGUAUCUACACUUCUUUUCACAUAAGUCUCUCGCAAGAGGGCCUUCUCUAACUGGCCCACACAGGCUCCUGAGUCCAGGUGGGAGCCUGUCUAGCCAGUUUACAAUUGAUGACAUGGUACUUGGAAGUGAGAUGUCAGGAAAAGGGAGUGUGGGUCAGAAGAUAGUCCAGUUUCAGAAUGGCCACACUGUUCUGAGACCAAGUGUGGAGCCACAUCUGGUGUAUCCAGCUUUGGGAGGUGGAGGAAGGCCUCAGCAUGGCGGGUGGUGCAGAUACCCUUUAUCCAGUAGCUACAUGGUUGUCCAUGUAUCCAAGUCACCACACCCAGCACUCUGGGAAGAAAGAAUCACAUUCUGCCAAAGUAAUUUCUCAGUUAAAUUUCAGUCUACUGGUGGCACACUCAGAGUAGUCAUUUUUUGACAUAUGAUUUAAUAGCUUUAUUUAUAUAUCUAAUAACGCUCGCAUAUAUGCUCUCUGGAAAAUAUUUUUGUAUAUAGAAGAGACAUCCUUAAUUGUGAUUUUUAUAAUGCUGAAACUCUGUCUUCUGUGACCUCUAUAAUAACUUCUGAAUCCAUCUAGUCUGACCCAGUCAUCUACUUCAAAUGAUAAUAAAUCAGAAAAUGUGGAAAACAAAAAAGCUCAAAACACAUCUCUUGGAAUAUAGAGUUGGAAAAGGGUCUGCCAGACUGCUUUGUUCUAAACCAAUUCAGAUGGUCCAGUGUAAUUCACAAUGGUUUAAACCUCUAGAUUUGAAGUCAUUACAUCCCAGAUGCAGACCCUGGCCAGCUCCCUAAGCUGUGUGGGCAGUGAGGUCCCAGAAGCUCUGCUGUUUGAGUUAUCUAAGCAGGGUUUUACAGAGUGAAUUCAAAUUCACUUUAAAGCUACUUGAACCUACAUGUCGAUAAACUCAGUUGUAGGGUUUGGCUUGCUGGAUAACUGUCAUGUUUCUCCACCACAGCAUUUUAUUGCCACCAAUUAAUGCUUAUUGAACAGUUGCAGCCUGUCCUUGUAGUAAGGGGUAACGAGGAUUGCAUAGAGAUACGACCUAAGGAUCAUGACAUUUGGAUGGUGGUAAAAUGCUAAAGGCCUUUGUUGGUCACAGCCCAGUUCCUGGCUCCCAUUCUAAAGGGACAGAGACAUACCAGAGAGUGAGCACCAUGUGGUCAAGUUGCUGAAGGGUCUGAAACCGUAAAGGAAGAGCUGAAGGAGCUGGGGCUGUUUCAUCUGGGAGGGGAACUCUAAAUGUUUGAAAGAUGUGGAAGAGAAGCUGGGUCAGGAACAAAAAUAGGAGCAAUGGGUGUAAGUUGCAUCAACGUAGAUUCUGGCAUUCUAACAACAUGAUUCAAAAGUGGAAGGUGAUGUUGGGAGCUUUUGGUGUUUGAGCAGAAAUUCUGAGCCUAUAUGUGUGAGGGGGGAUCUUUGAUUAAUUAAAACAUCUUCCUCACAGUAUGCAGGAACAUGGUAAAAGAAAGCAUUUACUACUUUUGUAAACAUUUUGGAUUGAAGAGAACUUUUCCAUCAUCCUGAAAAUCACUUUCAACUCCUGGGAUCAGAGAAAUAGCAGUGAAUACACCGAAGUCUGGCCUAAGAGGGUCAGAUCUAACCACAGGGCCAGAUUAUAGAGAAAAAUGAAAGCUCAAGAAGAAACCCCAUAAUAUCUGCAGCUGCCUCAAAAAGGUGGUUAAUUUCCACCCCCACCUACACUCCUGAAGGUCCUUUCCUAGUUGCUUUGAAACUAAUGGCUAAAAUUAGAUUUUGGGUGGCAUUCUUGUGGAGAAUAAAUCUCUCAGUCUUUACAUCUCUCCCAACAUCUCUGCCUCCUUCUUUCUGCUUAUUUAUAAAGCAUACUGCUUAUUGUCCAUUAAAACAUCAUUUGAAUGAGGAUGGGAGAGGAGAAUCGUACCAUGUAUGGCUUUUCUGAGAAGCCUUGGCAGAUCACAGACCCAGGACUUUAAACAGAGUGCUGUGCCGAUAACACUGCAUAGCAGGACCCAUUUAAUCUUGCCUUUGGUGGUUUACUUUACAGGAGACCAAGCUCUUGUGGCUACACAAAACAUAGACCAAAUAAAGGCAUCUUUGGGGGCUGGAUGUCCAUAGCAGCACCUCAUGGUUAGUGGUCCCAGGGAGGGCAUUUUCUCUACCAAGCAGUGUCCUGGCUCAGAUGGGUGCCAGCUGGCAUAUAUAUGGACAAUUUGGCAUUUCAUUGAUUUGAUCAUAAGGAACAAAUAGUUCCGCAAACACCCUAUUUCCUUUGAUAUGGUAACAUUUGAGUAACUCCAAAGCCAGAGAGGCAAUCUUUUCUAUCUCUGGUUUGUCAGAUUUUCUGCCGUUUUUCAGCCAGGCACUUUAAGAAUUCUUAAUUUGUUGUUCGUUAUUGAUUCAGGUCCUUUAAAAAUAGAGUUAAACACCCUCAUCUCAGAAGACAUGGAAUAAUAUCAAAAGUAAAGCCACCCACUGGCUGCAUCAGAAAAGAAGAGGGAGGCCGGGCGCGGUGGCUCACGCCUGUAAUCCCAGCACUUUGGGAGGCCGAGGCGGGUGGAUCACGAGGUCAGUAGAUCAAGACCAUCCUGGCUAACACAGUGAAACCCCGUCUCUACUAAAAAUACAAAAAAUUAGCCGGGCGUGGUGGCGGGUGCCUUAGUCCCAGCUACUCGGGAGGCUGA